CUUUAUUGGGAGAAAAAGUGCUUAGAGUGUUCAGUUAUUUUUUAUAUUUUUCUAAUUCAUUUCUUCUCUGGUUACAAAUCAGUCAUGCAUGGAUGUUUUAUUUUUUCUGAAAUCUCCAAGCACUUUAAGCAAAGGUUUUUAUUAGCCCACUUGAGUAGUGUGUUCAUGGGAGUAUACUUCCAUUGCGAAAGAAGUAUUGGUUUACUUGUAUCCAGAAGUUUUAGUUACUCUUGCCUGUACUGUAUUCUAGGUCUGUACUAGCAUUAUAAUUUUCCAUCUUUCUCCUGUCCUUUGAGUACCUUAUUUUUUCUUUUAGAAAUUUGGUUUGUCUUUAAUGGACUGAGAGGAAUCUUUUCCUUUCUUUCUCCGGGUUCUGAUUUUUUUUAAAGGUCUAUUAACAAUUUGUGCUUACUGUUGUUAGUAUUCUUGUGUGCUUGGCUUUAUCAGGCAUCCUACAAUGUAAUGUUGGUUAGAUGGGAAUUAGAGGUGCUUGGAGGUUGGCUAUGUCUGCCAACAGGCAGGAGGCCCCAAACUAACGUUUCCCAGUUCCAUUAAAGGUUUCUAGAGCAUAACUACUCUUCCUGUUUCAUCUACCCCCUCCAUACCCUCUUUGCUAACAUUCUCAGUAGAUCUUAAUAAGCAGAUGUCUGGAAUUACAGCAGAUUUUACCUCAAACAGUAUUUUCAGAUUUAGAAUUUCUGUAUCAUUUUUAGGUGUUAUGAAAUCCAAUCUAGGUGUAAUGGAGUAAGAGAGUAAAUAUUUCUUUUUCCUAAAUACUAUUUGAAAAGAAGUCUGAAAAUAGUGUGUUCCUCCACCCCCCCACCCAUGCCCAUCCUGCCAGUUUAGGAGCACUUUUGAUUCUUUUUUUUCUUUUUCUUUUUUUUUUUGAGAUGGAGUUUCACUCUUGUUGCCCAGACUGGAGUGCAAUGACACAAUCUCAGCUCACCACAACCUCUGCCUCCUGGGUUCAAGCGAUUCUCCCGCCUCAGCCUCCCGAGUAGCCGGGAUUAUAGACUGGCAUAAGGUCCCAGCUGGUGAUAUGAAGAGGUGGCUACAACUGUAAUAACAACCUGUAAUCUCUCUUGAAGAAAAGAGGACAGAGCUCACAGUGAUCAUGCAGCUGGAAAGUGCAGGAGAAAAUCCUAGAAAGAAUGUUGGAGUGGCAGAACCCCAAACACUGUUUAUAAACUCUGCUUGAAUUUCUUGCAAACCCCUCAACUGUACAUGUGUGGAGCAGCCUCCAAACAGCACACUUAAGGCUAAAGGAGCAGAGAUUUCAGCUGCUGUCCACCAUAGGGGAGGCAGAACUUGGAGUUUAAGUCCAGCUAAGAACCACAAUGGACACUGCCAGCCAUAGCCUUGUUCUUCUCCAGCAGCUGAACAUGCAGCGAGAAUUUGGUUUUCUGUGUGAUUGCACAGUUGCAAUUGGAGAUGUUUACUUCAAAGCCCACAGAGCAGUGCUUGCUGCUUUUUCUAACUAUUUCAAGAUGAUAUUUAUUCACCAAACAAGUGAAUGCAUAAAAAUACAACCAACUGACAUCCAACCUGACAUAUUCAGCUAUUUGUUGCACAUUAUGUACACGGGGAAAGGGCCAAAACAGAUUGUGGAUCAUAGUCGUUUGGAGGAAGGGAUUCGAUUUCUUCACGCCGACUACCUUUCUCACAUUGCAACUGAAAUGAAUCAAGUGUUCUCACCAGAGACUGUGCAGUCCUCAAAUUUAUAUGGCAUUCAGAUCUCAACAACCCAAAAAACAGUUGUCAAACAAGGACUGGAGGUCAAAGAAGCUCCUUCCAGUAACAGUGGAAACAGAGCUGCUGUCCAGGGUGACCACCCCCAGUUGCAGUUGUCUCUUGCUAUUGGUCUGGAUGAUGGCACUGCAGACCAGCAGAGGGCCUGUCCUGCCACCCAGGCCCUGGAGGAGCACCAGAAGCCCCCAGUUUCCAUCAAGCAGGAGAGAUGUGACCCAGAAUCUGUGAUCUCCCAGAGCCACCCCUCACCCUCAUCAGAGGUGACAGGCCCCACUUUUACUGAAAACAGUGUCAAAAUACACUUAUGCCAUUACUGUGGGGAACGUUUUGAUUCCCGUAGUAACCUAAGGCAACAUCUCCAUACACAUGUGUCUGGAUCCCUGCCAUUCGGUGUCCCUGCUUCCAUUCUGGAAAGUAAUGACCUUGGUGAAGUGCAUCCCCUUAAUGAAAACAGCGAGGCCCUUGAAUGCCGCAGGCUCAGCUCCUUCAUUGUUAAGGAGAAUGAACAGCAGCCAGACCACACCAACCGGGGUACCACAGAGCCUUUGCAGAUCAGUCAAGUAUCUUUGAUCUCCAAAGACACAGAGCCAGUAGAAUUAAACUGUAAUUUUUCUUUUUCAAGGAAAAGAAAAAUGAGCUGUACCAUCUGUGGUCAUAAAUUCCCUCGAAAGAGCCAAUUGUUGGAACACAUGUAUACACACAAAGGUAAAUCUUACAGAUAUAACCGAUGCCAAAGGUUUGGUAAUGCAUUGGCCCAGAGAUUUCAGCCAUACUGUGACAGCUGGUCUGAUGUCUCCCUGAAAAGUUCUCGCUUGUCACAAGAACACUUAGACUUGCCUUGUGCCUUAGAGUCAGAGCUCACACAAGAAAAUGUGGAUACUAUCCUAGUUGAGUAGCAGCUUCUCUUUCAGAAUUUUUAUACCAAUUCUGAAAAAGAAAAUUUGCGUGGCAUUUUUAAUUCAUAAAUUAUUUUCCUCCUCAAGUUUCAUUGACUUUUUUUCUUCACAGCUUAUCCAUGGUUUUAAGGUUGUAUAUAUUAGAUCUUCUCAUAAGACAUAUUAAUAUGUGGCUAUUAAAAUGUAACAUUCAAUUACUACUGUGAACUUUUCACAAACGAAAUAACAAUUUAGAAAUCAGAAAUCAAUGUAGAAAUAUGGAAACCUUAAAUAGUUAUUUAUAGAAUUCUAAGUUUUUCCAGUUAUAGAAUCAGUAAAAUCAAAUUGAAUAUAAAGUAAAUGAAAUCUGUUUUAAAGCAUAUUCUAAACUAUCACUUCUGCCUACAUUUCACAUGAAUUCACUCCUACCAGGAUUAUUUUUAAAUAUUUUCUUCCAUAUAGGAAAUUAAUAGUUACUUUAAUGCAUAACUGUAUGUUAUACAUAUGUUAUAAUGUAUAAAAAUUUAUUUUAAGAUAUACCAAAUCAUGAGUAGUUUUAUUUUUUAACUACUAGCUCCACAACAUCUUACCUACAUGGCUUCUCUUUACUUUUUAACAUUGAGUAUACCUCUUUUUUUUUUUGAGACAGAGUCUCUCUGUGUCGCCCAGGCUGGGGCGCAGUGGCGCGAUCUCGGCUGACUGCAAGCUCCGCCUCCCGGGUUCACGCCAUUCUCCUGCCUCAGCCUCCUGAGCAGCUGGGACUACAGGCGCCCGCCACCACGCCCAGCUAAUUUUUUUGUAUUUUUUUAGUAGAGACGGGGUUUCACCGUGUUAGCCAGGAUGGUCUCGAUCUCCUGACCUCGUCAUCUGCCCGCCUUGGCCUCCCAAAGUGCUGGGAUUACAGAUGUGGUAUAUCUCAUUUUUAAUAAAAAAAACAGUUAAAGGGAGAAGAGUCAGAGAGACAUUAAAAAAUAUUUAAGAAACAGUAAGAUAUACACACAUAGAUAAAUAAGCAUGCAGAGACAGAGACUGAGCUAGAACUGCAUUGACUAAAAACCCCAGGGUUGUUAACUUGGUCUAGAGUGUUUUCUUAGACACCUUAAAAAGUAAUUUGAGAUUUUAUGACCAGAGGUUUACAUGAGUUGAAAGAGAAUGAUGAUAAAAUAUAAAUCAUGUUUCUACCCUCAGCGUCAGGAUUUUUGGGGCUUCCUGGGUUGAUUUUAAUUUUCUAAAAAUCACUGAAAAAGUAAUUUUUCAGUGGCACAGUUUUCACUUUUUUCCUGAUCCAUAAAACCAGCAAAGUGGAUACAUUCAGUGUUCUAUAACUACAUUUAAGAUCCAUGAUGUUAGCUUUUCCUCUAUAAAUCAACUUAACUCUCUUUUAUAAUGGUGACACUUACAAAGCUAAAACCCCAGGAAAAUUAAAGUUGAUGAAAGAAAUAACAGAUUCCCCGGCUCUAUAUACCUGGGAAAUAGCUGGUUAAGCUUCACCACAAAGGAUAGAUCUAAAUUGUUUCUGAAAUGUUUAAAUUUCAAACCCCGCAUAGUCAAGGAUAAUAAAACAGACUCAUCUUUUUUUGCCCUCUUGUUAAAUUCUAAGCUUCACGGGCAUUUGAAUACAUCUAAAAAAUUUGGUUUGUGAGCCUUAGAAUUUAACCACUUACAAAACUCUUGAGCUCCCUCCACUUCUGAGGACGUUUCCUGACACAUUCAACAGCAUCAGCGUCCAAUCAGGAGGGAGCUCAAAGAGUAAUCCAGCUAAUUCUAAGGACACAAAGGUUUUCUCUAGGUAAACAGUUUAGGUAAAUUACAAAGUGGUAAGUUUUUCUUGAGGAUUGAAUGAAGAAAGCUACUGGAUAUUGUGUAAGGCAGUUGAGUUUCUGCCUUAAACAAGUGAGUAAAGGCUCCUAUGGUUAAGACUGAUGUGUGUUGAGAGCACAUCUAACUUGAUAAGAUCAAUUGUAUUGGGAGUAAUUAAAACAAAUGUAUGUUCUUUGGGGUCAGAACUUUGUCUAAUCUUAAACUUUUUUCUACCAAUUCACUUAAGCAACUAUUGAAAUUUGUACUGCCCUCAAAAAUAUCAUCUCAUUGGAAGAACACAAGUAUUAACAUUGAUUUUUUGUAUUUUAGGCUAGUUAAGAUAUAUUUCCUAGCCUUCUUCAAUUCAAAUUCUAUUGUUCUUAUUAAGAUAAUUUUUCUCCUCUAUAUUCUUCCCUGUUUGCCUACUCAUUAUUAUUAUUUUUUUAAUUUAAUUUUUUUUUAAGAUGGAGUUUCACCCUUGUUGCCCAGGCUGGAGUGCAAUGGCGUGAUCUCGGCUCACUGCAAUCUCUGCUGCCUGGGUUCAAGCGAUUCUCCUGCCUUAGCCUCCCAAGUAGCUUGGGAUUACAGGCAUGCACCACCAUACCCAGCUAAUUUUGUGUUUUUAGCAGAGACAGGGUUUCACCAUCUUGGUCAGGCUGGUCUGGAACUCCUGACCUCAGGUCAUGCACCAGCCUCGGCCUCCCAUAGUGCUGGGAUUACAGGUGUGAGCCACCGUGCCAGGCCCACUCAUUAUUCUUUGACACAGGAAAUCCUUGUAUAUAGCUAAAGGGUGGAGGUAGAGUUGUACAUGGUUGGUUGGAUAAGACAGCAAGUGCCUCAGGGCAGAGUUUGGAUAAAUGGUAAGAGUUUGCUAGCAGCUGAUUGGCCGUGAUAGACAACACUCAUUUAAAGCAGAAAUAUAUCUGUUCGUUGAGAGUUAAGAAAAUAGUGGUUAACUGUAUUUCUAUUCUUAUAGUUCCUUUUAAUAUUAGAAAUUCAAAGCAAAUGCUCUUUCCUUGUUCCUUAAAACAUUCAUUCUGUUUAGGAAGUGGGAAAAUAUCAACUUCAUUUUAUAGAAAAAAAAUCCCAAAAGCUGAAUUCCAGAGAUGCAGUGAAUAGUGGUGUGGGACUGACCCCCAGUUUUUGUUAUUGUUGUUUUCAUUUAUUCUGCAGGCUUUUUUUUUUUUUUUUUUUUUUUUUUUUGAGACAGUCGUGCUGUGUCGCCAGGCUGGAGUGCAGUGGUGCAAUCUCAGCUCACUGCAACCUCCGCCUCUCGAAUUCAAGUGAUUCUCCUGCCUCAGCCUCCUGAGCAUGUGCCACCAUGCCCAGCUAAUUUUUGUAUUUUUAGUAGAGACAGGGUUUCACCAUGUUGGCCAGGAUGGUCUCGAGCUCCUGACCUCAUGAUCUGCCUGCCUCAGAUUACAGGCAUGAGCCACCGCGCCCGGGUCUGCAGGCAUUUUUUAAAGUAACUGUCAUAUGCCUAACACUGUGCCCUGAGUAUUAUUUUUUAAAGACAUGAUUGCUCACUGAGAAAAUUUGCUUUGUAUUUUAAAAGUUCUUCCAGCUAGGCCAGGCGUGGUGGCUCAUGCUUGUAAUCCCAGCACUUUGGGAGGCCGAGGCGGGCGGGUCACGAGGUCAGAAGAUCCAGACCAUCCUGGCUAACACAGUGAAACCGCGUCUCUACUAAAAAUACAAAAAAUUAGCCGGGUGUGGUGGCACACACCUGUAAUCCCAGCUACUCGAGAGGCUGAGGCAGUGGAAUAGCUUGAACCCGGGAGGCAGAGGUUGCAGUGAGCGGAGAUCGCACCACUGCACUCCAGCCUGGGUGACAGAGCGAGACUCCAUCUCAAAAAAAAAAAAGUUCUUCCAGCUAAAACCUUUAUUUUUUGACUACAUCUCCACAAAAUGGAGCUAUACUGUUAGCCAGUAUCCUAAUAGUAUAGUGCAGUUUGCAUAAUGAUUACCAAGCUUGAAACUGGAAAUGUCAUAUGCACUUUCGUGUGUAUCAGGCAGAUACUAAACAUUUUCCCCUUGAGUCAGCUUAAAAUUUUUCCUUCUUUUGAAAUCUCACGCAGUUGUUUUCUGGAGAAAAAUAGAGACUGUUUUAGUAUUUGUUCUUAUUAGCGUAUCAUCAGAACUCAGCACAGUCUGCCUUAUAAGAAAACAAAAAAUUUUUUUAUUUAUAACUCUUGAGAUUGUUACUUCUUGCUCUUUCUGAUUUCCCAUCCGUAAAGUGGGUGUAAGCAAUACUUACCUCACAGGGGUGUUGUGAGGAUUUAUAUUAAACGUGUUAAGUUCUCUCAGUAUUAUUGAUUAAAAUCAACCAUAUAAACGACAUUUAUUCUGUAGCUAGACCUAUUAACUUUAGUAUUUCAGCCUAUAAAUUCUAAAAUGUUCUUAAAAGCAGUAAUGUACUAUCUAAUAUUCAAUAACUAAUUGACAGAACUCAUUGUUAUUUUUUACAAAUAACUAGAAACAAUACUGUUGCUAGAAUUCCUGUUCUACUGUAAUUUAAUCAUCACUGUUUCUUUUUAGCCUUCAGUAAGGAGGAUACUAGUUCUUUGGCAUUAUUGGGAAUAAAACUUUGUCAAUUUCAGCUUUAUUGAAAGUUCUCCCAAAUAUAUUGUUUUUGUUUACACAAAGGAAAAGGAACAAAAACAAUAAAUAAAUACCUUUGUUUUUUUUUCUUUUUUGAGACGGAGUCUCGCUCUGUUGCCCAGGCUGGAGUGCAGUGGUGCGAUCUCGGCUCACUGCAACCUCCGCCUCCCAGGUUCAAGCGAUUCUUCUUCCUCAGCCUCCCGAGUAGCUGGAACUAUAGGCACGCACCACCACACCCAGCUAAUUUUUGUAUUUUUAGUAGAGAUGGGGUUUCAUCAUGUUGGCAAGGCUGGUUUCGAACUCCUGACCUUGUGAUCUGCCUAUCUCAGCCUCCCAAAGUGCUGGGAUUACAGGUAUGGGCCACUGGGCCCAGCCUAUUUUUAUUUCUUUGAUGUAGGUGAUCUAAAUAGUAGAUGAGGACAGGAAAUGGGGUGAAGGUAAUAAUAGUAUUAUUAGAAAAGUCUUCACUGAAAAUUGAAGGAAAUACAUAUUAAUCGUGGAAAAAGAUAGUGUGAAAAAUGUGUAAUUUCGUUAACAUUUAUUUGUACAGGCACAUUCUUGAUGUUGUGAGUCAGAUACUUGAUAAAUGUCCAUUUUUUGUAGUAAUUGAUGUAAAAAUGGGCCAUGUGAAGAAUUUUCAUAAUGUAAUUUGUGUCUUUGUAUAUUUUGAACUACAUAUAGAUUUGUGGCACUUAAAUUAUUAAUUUUUGAUUUCUUAAGAGUGAAGUCUGUAAAUGAUUUCUCUCUGCUGUACUUCUGUGUUUGUAUGGUUGGACAUUUUGAAAACUGGUGAGAUUGCACAGUCCCAAACCUGGAUGUCUUAAAUACAAGGAAUUACAAACUGUGAUUUUUGUCUUGAAGACCUGGAAGAAUUCAUUGUGCUUCAGUAUGUAUUUGUACUGCACUUGAUUAAUUAGUUAAGUAUUGGUCUGGUGCAAUUGACAUUAACUGUCAUCAACUCCUCUAUUUUGUGCUAAAUAAAGUCAUUUAGUCAGAAUGGAUCAAAUAUAAACUUAUACUUUAAAAUAAACUUAGAUUAUAAAAACUUGUUCAAUAAAAAAGACCCACUGAAAAAUCUUCAAAGUACAUGUAACACAUAGCUAAUACAGGAGACCAAAAUCAAUAAUACAUUGUGUGGCUAAACUCAUCCACCUAAUGUACUGUGAAUUUGCUUCAGAAACAUUCUUUUAGAAAGUUGUGUAUCUGCCGGGCAUGGUGCCUCAUGCCUGUAAUCCCAGCACUUUGGGAGGCCAAGGCCCAGGAGUCCGAGACCAGCCUGGGCAAUAUAGUGAGACCUCAUCUCUGCCAAAAAUUUUGGCCAGGGGCAGUGGCUCACGCCUGUAAUCCCAGCACUUUGGGAGGUCGAGGUGGGCGGAUCACCAGAGGUCAGGAGUUCAAGAUCAGCCUGGCUAACAUGGCGAAACCCUGUCUCUACUAAAAAUACAAAAAUAAGCCAGGUGUGGUGGUGCGCGUCUGUAGUCCCAGCUACUUGGGAGGCUGAGACAGAAUCAUUUGAACCCGGGAGAUGGAGGUUGCAGUGAGCCGAGAUUGCGCCAUUGCACUCCAGCCUGGGCGACAGAGUGAGACUCCGUCUCAAAAAAAAAAAGGCAGGGUGUGGUGGCUCACACCUGUAAUCCCAGCACUUUGGGAGGCCAAGGCGGGCGGAUUAUGAAGUUAGGAGAUCGAGACCAUCCUGGACAACAUGGUGAAACCCUGUCUCUAGUAAAACACAAAAAAUUAGCUGGGUGUGGUGGCACGUGCCUGCAGUCCCAGCUACUAGGGGGGCAGAGGCAGAGGAAUUGCUUGAACCCGGGAGGCGGAGGUUGCAGUGAGCCGAGAUUGCGCCACUGCACUCCAGCCUGGCGACAGAGCAAGAAACAAUGAAUUUCAUAUAUUUUAUCAAGACAAAUUAAUGUGACUUAAUCAAAAACAAGUUUAUUAGCUUAGCUUAUAGAAUGUGUUCUUAUUUUACAUCAGUGUUUGCCAAAUGUUGUGUUCCUAGUGUUGAGGCAAGUAGUCUUUGUACUGGGUAACAUUUUGGAGGUGUGAUGCAAAAAUGCAUUUGUGGACCUAAUUCUUACCGACCAUAAUCUGUGUUAAUCGAAAAUUGACGUCCUAAUCAAAUGCUUUCCAACUGCUGUCUCUGGAAAGAAAGGUAGUAUUUCGUCAUUUCCCAGAAGUUUCUUGCUUUGCUUCUUCUUUUUUUUUUUUUUUUUUUUUUUUGAGAUGGAGUCUUGCUCUGUUGCCCAGGCUGGAGUACAGUGGAGUGAUCUCGGCUCACUGCAACCUUCACAUCCCAGGUUCAAGCUAUUCUCCUGCCUCAGCCUCCCGAGUAGCUGAGAUUACAGGUUCCCACCACUACACUCGGCUAAUUUUUUGUAUUUCUAGUAGAGACGGAGUUUCACCAUGUUGGCCAGGCUGGUCUCGAACUCCUGACCUUGUGAUUCACCUGCCUCAGCCUCCCAAAGUGCUGGGAUUACAGGCGUGAGCCACCGCGCCCAGCUGCUUCUUUCUUCUCUAUUUACAGUCUACUGUAUCGCCUUUUGCCCCCAGUAACAUGAUCCACAAUAGUAGUUCUCAACUGAGGUAUAUUAGUCAGGAUUCUCCAGAAAAAGAAAGAAACAACAGGUAGAACUGAGAGAGAGAAAGAGAUUGAUUGAUUAUAAGGAAUAGGUUCAUGUAAUUAUGGAGGCUGAGAAGUCCCAAGAUCUGCAGUUGGGAGGCUGAGAGGCUGGGGAGUCAGUGAUGUUCCAAUCUGAAUUUGAAGACCUGAGAACCAGGAGAGCUUAUGGCAUAAGUUCCAGUCCAAAAGCUGGCAGGCUUGAAACUCAAGAAGAGCUGAUGUUUCCAUUUGGGUCCAAAGGGAAGAAAAGACCGAUAAUUGCAGCUCAAGCAGUCAGGCCAGAGAAAGUCUCUUUUUUUAUUAUAUUCUGGCCUUCAACUGAUGGAAUGAGAGCCACCCACAUCAGGGAGGGUGAUCUUCUUUACGCAGUCUACUGAUUCAGAUUUUGUCUCCCUCCAGAACACCCUCACGGACACACCCAGAAUAAUGUUUGACUAACUAUUGGGGCAGCCCAUGGCCCAGUCAUUUGGACACAUAAAAUUAAACAUUACACAGGGCUAUCCCCCCCCAUAGAGACAUUUGACGAUGUGGAGAUGUUUUUGGUUGUCACAGUUGGGUGGGCGAUGAGGGAGGCUGCUGCUGGCAUCUAGUAGGUGGAGGCCAGGGAUGCUGCUAAACAUCUCAGUGCAGAGGACAGCCUCCCGCAAUACAGAAUAUGUACCUCAAAAUGUCAUUAGAGCUGAGGUUGACCAACCCUUCUGAGACCUUAAAGUAAGUUUUGUGAUGGCUGUCAGGAAUAAAAGAAUACAAAGAAACCCAAUUUGGGGGAUUUCUAUUCUAGUCAUGUUUAGAGCAAGUAUUGGAGUAUGAGAUGUGUUCAGAAUUAAAUUCUAUUUGUAUUAUCCUUGAUCCCAGCUUUUAAAAGAUAAAAAUGUGAUUAUUAGAAAUAAAAGGAAAAAAUGUGAUUAUUAAAAAUCAGAGAUGUAUUAAUCAGCAAGACAGUUUUGAAUCUAUUCAUAUAAUGUUUGAACUAAAUAAUUGUCUCCCCAAAGAGGUCUCUUCAUGAAAUUGAGAUUGUAGGUUAUAAUUUCUGUGAAUUUUUAAUCUGGCCAAAAGGUGGCACCAGUGUACCUUUAAAAAAAUGUUCAUUAUACUUGAAUUCAGCAUUACUAUUAAUAGUAAAUAUUAUUUAGGGCUUAGCUACUUUUGGAUCAUGCUUUAUAGAGUCAAGACUAAUGAGAAUUUUCUUAAAAUUUCAUAAGGUACUGCAAUAUCUUGACAUCCCUCUUUAAUCAAGAUGCUUCUGAUUUACAUGUACAUAUCUCAGCAGAUAACUUUUUAAAAUAUCACAUUAUUGUGCUACAUUGAGCAUUUCUGAAGAUUUUUCCAAGCCAUUAACUGUGAGGCCUUGGAAUUUGGGCUCUUUUAAUCAGGCAUCACACUCAGUUUUUGGUGUUCUGCCUGGUCAAGACAUAGAUUGAAGGACAUUUGAGUAAAUACGCUCCCUUGCUCCUUUCUUGCCUUUUGUUCAUUUUUUGUACAUCCACAAUCUAUGAGGUAUGUUACCUACUGAAAUUUACUUUCUUUUCCAACUGUGGUUCAACAACUGACUUUCUUCUCUCAUACUUUCCAACCCAUUCCAUUCUGAAUAAGUUAAGAGUUUUCUUACCUUCAGCUCUUCUCACCUUCCAAUACUAAGUGAAUACAGCCUGCCUCCCCCUUCAUUUCUGAUUACAAUAUUAUUCUCAUCAUCCUAGGACUUUGUACCUAAUCACCAGUUGCUUCUCCUAAGUUUAUUUUACAGCUGAUAAGCCAACUUGGAAAAUGAGCCCACUCUCCCUCAGAUACAUUCUCUUCCGCUGUUUGAAACGUUUUUCAUUGAAACAAUUUGGUGAUAUUGUAUCAAAAUAAUAAAGUAUUAAGCUACUGGAA